AGUGCUUUCUGCUAGUUCAAUCCCAUUGUGAUUUAAAUACUUAAUAAUGUGUCCUUUAGACAUGAAUUUGAACAGAAUCUAACACGUCUGCUACCACCGACUUAGAGAUUUCCACUAUUUGCAGGGCUUUAAAAUCCCCUGGCUAAACUCCUAUUUUUUUAAUGCCACACGCAUUGAAUUCAUGAAUGUUAUCAGUCUUUUUAAUAAAAUAUUGCCCAUUUUACAACAUUUCCACCCUGCAUAAAUAGAGAUGAUGCUGCUAGCUCACCAUUAGAGUGAGGGAAAAUUUCACCUUUGUCCUCUGAAAUUUCACAGAAAUCAACUGACAAAUGGCAGAUUCAUAGGAGAAAAGACAUACACAUUUAUUUGAUCAUAGUUUUACAUAACAGAGGAGCCUUCAGAUGAGAAUCCAAAGAUACAAGAGAAACUUCCCAUUUUUAUGCUUAGGUUCAAAGCCAUAUGGACAGCCAUGUAGAAAUAUGAUUGAACAUGAAGGGCAUGAUCUAAUACUGAUGGACUGAGUGAAGAAGCCCAGCAAGACCCAUCGUGAGAUUCUUUUUGGCCUCUCUGAGCAGUGUUCCUUUUUUCUUGGUAUGCAAUAAGACCUCUCUGGAAUGGAGGUCUUAUGAUCUACAAUCCAGUAAGGUGGCCUUUUGCCCCACCCCCAGCAUACAAUGAUGGAAAUAGCCAAUGUGAGUUCUCCAGAAGUCUUUGUCCUCCUGGGCUUCUCCACACGACCCUCACUAGAAACUGUCCUCUUCAUAGUUGUCUUGAGUUUUUACAUGGUAUCGAUCUUGGGCAAUGGCAUCAUCAUUCUGGUCUCCCAUACAGAUGUGCACCUCCACACACCUAUGUACUUCUUUCUUGCCAACCUCCCCUUCCUGGACAUGAGCUUCACCACGAGCAUUGUCCCACAGCUCCUGGCUAACCUCUGGGGACCACAGAAAACCAUAAGCUAUGGAGGGUGUGUGGUCCAGUUCUAUAUCUCCCAUUGGCUGGGGGCAACCGAGUGUGUCCUGCUGGCCACCAUGUCCUAUGACCGCUACGCUGCCAUCUGCAGGCCACUCCAUUACACUGUCAUUAUGCAUCCACAGCUUUGCCUUGGGCUAGCUUUGGCCUCCUGGCUGGGGGGUCUGACCACCAGCAUGGUGGGCUCCACGCUCACCAUGCUCCUACCGCUGUGUGGGAACAAUUGCAUCGACCACUUCUUUUGCGAGAUGCCCCUCAUUAUGCAACUGGCUUGUGUGGAUACCAGCCUCAAUGAGAUGGAGAUGUACCUGGCCAGCUUUGUCUUUGUUGUCCUGCCUCUGGGGCUCAUCCUGGUCUCUUACGGCCACAUUGCCCGGGCCGUGUUGAAGAUCAGGUCAGCAGAAGGGCGGAGAAAGGCAUUCAACACCUGUUCUUCCCACGUGGCUGUGGUGUCUCUGUUUUACGGGAGCAUCAUCUUCAUGUAUCUCCAGCCAGCCAAGAGCACCUCCCAUGAGCAGGGCAAGUUCAUAGCUCUGUUCUACACCGUAGUCACUCCUGCGCUGAACCCACUUAUUUACACCCUGAGGAACACGGAGGUGAAGAGCGCCCUCCGGCACAUGGUAUUAGAGAACUGCUGUGGCUCUGCAGGCAAGCUGGCGCAAAUUUAGAGACUCCAGUGCCUUCUGAGAAGGAAGAUCAAGUUUACAUCGAGCAAAGUGACCUUGGAAGACAGGGCACUUGGGAUGUCGUUUUUCUUCUAAUAUUGUUUGAGCUCAAGGUAGAUGGAAAUCUGAAAGGAGUGUGCUCAUGCCAUUUCCAGACCAAGAAAAUACAUUUAUUAUUUGCUAAUUAUCAUAGUUUUGUUCAAUUGCGUUGUUGGUUUUUGCUAUAUAUACACAUGUUGACUGUCAUCUUGUUUUGUAAACUCCUUGCGUUGUUGUUCAGCUGUUCCUCAGUAUCCGAAGCGGGUGGAUUCCAGGACGCUCCGUGGAUAAUAAACUUUGACGACGCUGAGAGCGCGCGGGGAGACCGGAGCCGGCCUGUUCCCCAGAGCCCCCGGAGCCCUCCCAGCCCUCAGGCCUGCGCCUGGGGUGAGCUGAGCCCGGGACUCCGCCUUGCAGGCUCCGGAACCCUCGCUGUGGCUCCCCCGCUCGGCCCAGGCCUUGAAGCCGCGGCGAACCUCUUCCUACCCUACCUCGGGGACCUGGUGGCAGCGGCGGCCUCCCCCAGCCUGGACCCCGCCGGCCGCGGGUCUCCCGGCCCAACCCCACCGACCCAGACCAAGACCGCGCCGAGCCGCCGGGACUCAGCGCCUUCGGGUGGCGGCGGUAAGCGGGGAGGAAACAUGGCGCCGCCCAAAUGCGCCCGGAGGCCGUUAGGCUGUGGAGGGCGAGGAAGGCGGUCCAGAGGCGGCCGGCAGGUCCACGUCCUGGGCGACCGCUCUGUCGCAGUUGGGCGAGACCUACCUAGUCCUGACGGGUCGUAUUUCCAAGACAUUUUCAUAUUCUAUCCAUUGUUUUGUGUGCAUUUUAUUACUUCUGUAUAUAGAGGUAACAACGCUAAGCUUUUUUGAGAUGUCUGUUUCUUCUAGAUGUUCUGAAGUACCUGAUACAUGUUAAAAUUAGAGGUAGUAAAAUGACACAUUUUGUAAAUAACUUUUUGUUAAAAUUCAUAGGAAAUGUUAUUUUGUGGGGGGGGGAUGGCAUGGUGUUUGUGGACUGGUUCAGGGAAGGAGGGGAAAAGGGAGGUGCAGAGAGCUCUAAGCCAGUGUGCUUACAGUGAGGCGAGAUUCACCAUUGUUUCUUAUGAUUGUGCAUUUUGUUUUACUUAUCUAUGUAUACAGUGUAUCUAAAGGACAAACGAGUCCUAAUUUACAACAGCUAGUCUUUCCAGAUGUUAAAGAACUUCUAUCAAUAGAGUAACCUAUCACUAGAGUUCACCUCUAUCAAUAGAGUAACCUCAUUCUCUGCCUGAUGAUUCAAAGGCAUGGGAAGACCAAAACCAUGUGGCAGUUCCUGUUUUUGAUUUUAUUAUAUAUAUGUAUAUAAUAUGAAAGUAGUCAUUAAAGUAGUCUUUCCUUUCGUACUAGGAUCUUCCAAUUCACUGUAUUAGUCAGGGUUCUCCAGAGAAACAGAACCAAAAAUAUGUGUAAAAGAGAAUACACACACACACACACACCCUGAGGGGGAGAGAGAGAAAAAAGAGUGAGAGAGAUUGAGAGUUAAGAAAUAGGCUCACACAAUUUAGGGAACUGGCAAGUCUGAAAUUUGCAGGGCAAGCCAGCAGGCUGUAAAUUUUGACAGAGGUUGAUGUUGCAGCUUGAGUUCAAAGUCUGGAGGCAAAAUUCCCUCUUUUUGGAAGCAGGUCAGUCUUUUCUCUUAAGGCUUUCAACUGAUGGGAUGAGACCCACUCACAUUAUAAAGGGUAAUCUGCUUUACUAAAAGUCUACUGAUUUAAAUGUUAAUCGCAUCAAAAAAAAAAAAAAAAAAAAAAAAAAACACCUUCACAGUAACACCGAGGCUUGUGUUUGAACAAAAACUGGGCACCAUAGUCCAACCAAGUUGAUAUGUAAAAUGAACCAUCACACCAAACCCAAACUUUCAGUGAAGUGAAGCAACAUUCUUCAACUGGAUUAUUAUGCAUCAUGUACGAGACACUCUCAUGUCUUGUUGGUUUCUGGACUCAUGUAUCAGGUUACGGUGACUGCAGGUUUAGGGCAUACACUGCAGCCUGCAGGAAAGCAGUGCUUAUUUACACAGUAUUGUUUCUCAGCUUCAAUAACUAAACCUUCAGCAGGCCAUUCCAUCAUUCAAUAAAGCCCAUUCCAUCAUUCAGUCAAGCCCACUGCUUCUGAAUAUUGAGGUAUGAAGUAUGAAUCAUGAAUUCCAAGGGCAAUUCUAUUGCCACACCCCUUUUGCUGUGAAAUAUGUUUCCUGGUUACAGGUGAUAUUGCAGGGGAUGCCAUGGUGAUGAUUAAGGCUUUGUUCACUAUGUAAAUGGUUCGGGCAUGGAAGACAAAACUGUCCCCACAAUAUUAUUCUGUCCCUAUAAAGACUAACAUUGCUUACUCUAUGCUCAAAGGAGUCCAGAGUAAUCACUAUGCUACUAGUCCAGCCAGACGCCUGGAAAUAGUGCCAAAUCACAUGCUAACCUUGGUGAGAGAAAUGUCAUAAUGCUGAGCCCAUUCAUAGUUUCCAUCCCUGCUUCCAUGUUAAAUUUCUCAUAGGCUCAAUGAGCAAGCCUGCUGGCAAAAGAGAUUGACUGAUUACCUACUAGAUGAGUCAUCUUAUCUACCAUACCACCAAGAUCCAUCUCUGCAGUGGAUGCCCUCUCAUGGGCAUUUAUGUCAGACAGAUAUCUUCAUGAUCUGUGCACUUUUCAGGAAAUUCUUCAAUGUCCUCUUCUCCAGAUUUGCCUGCCAUUAAUUUUCCAGCCUUAUUCUUCACAAAUCUCUCAGCAAAAUAAUAACUUGUUAUCCAAUGCUCCUAAAUCAGUGCAUAUCCAAACUUCUGUGCCUGUCUCCUUCUAUAAAAAAUUAACAACCAGCUAAACUGCCUGUAGUUUGACCACUGGGAAGUUUCCCUUCCUCACCAUCUUUCAGCAACACCUGGAGGGGUACUGUGGUUUAAUGCCAUUUGCUUCUUUCUGUUGCUGGUGUAUAAUGCAGAUUCAUUUGUAAACUGGCCCAUGCUUUUUCCUUCUUUAACAGUUGGCUAAACAUGAAAUAUGGGUGAGAUCAUGCAGGAUUUGUCCCUUUGUGUUUGGCUUAUUUCACUUAACACAAUGUCUUCUAGGUUCAUGCAUGUUGUGAAGACAGGAUUUUGAACGCUCUCACCACAAAGAAAUGACAAGUGUUUGAGGUAAUGGAUAUGUUAAUUACCUUGAUUUGAUCAUUACACAAGUAUACAUGUAUCAAAACAUCAUACUGCACCCCAUAAGUGUGUACAAUUGUUAUUUGUGAAUUAAAAACAAACUAAAAUGAAAUUUAAAAAAUAAUUAUACAAUUUUGGGGGCUUGGGGGUGGGGGAAGGGGAAGUAAAAAAGCAGACAGCAGGUACUCUAGGAGUCAGAGACACAUGAUAACAUUAUUAUGAGUCAGGAAGGUAGGAAAUCAAGUUACUGACAUUUUUUACUCAGUUUAGAACCCAAAGACCGAAGAAACAGAAACAAAUGGGGGAAAUCAUAACUUUUAAAGUAUUAGAUAAAAUUUUUGAGAAAGUUAAAUACUGCAUGUUCUCAUUCAUCUGUGAAAGCUAAAAAAGGGUUGAUCUCAUAGAAAUAAGUAGAACAGAGGAUACUUGAGGCUGGGAAUGGAUAGCAGGGGUGGGGGAAUGAGAAGAGAUUUGUUAAAGGAUACAAAAUUACAGCUCCAUUGGAGGAGUAAGUUCUAGUGUUCUAUACCACUGCGGGAUGACCAUAACAAUAAUAUAUUCUGUAUUUUCAAACAGCUAGAAGGAGGAUAUUGAAUGUUCCCAGCACGAAGAAACGAUAAAUGUUUGAGAUGAUGGAUAUUCUAAUCACACUUAUCUGAUCACUAUACAUUAUGUGCUUCCAAACAUCACUGUUUACCCCAGAAAUAUGUUCAAUUAUUAUAUGUCCACUAAAAGCUAAAAUAAAAAAAUUUUCAAACAUUCAAGAUCUGAAGAAAAACUUCAAUCUGAAUACUAAAAACUUUCCCUAACCUCUUGAAAAGACUAAUUAAAAAUCUCUGGAGUUUGGAUGCACUGUAAUUUUCAUCUGCCAGUUCAUGGCUUUGUUUAAGCUCAGUAGUCAAGUUGGUAGAACCUCCAGAGAAAGCAAUGAGGAAGUGGCAGUAGGACCCUCUGGGACCCGUUACCCCAAAUAUCUGUCAUCUUCUUGACCUCAAGGCUGGGUGUCAACUCAGGACAGGAGUGCAGGUCCUCAUCAGUUUAUGUGGGGAUAGCAGACAACGCAGACCCUCCCAGAACCAUGAGGACAGCACUGUGCUUUGCCCUGACCAUCCAUCAGCCCCUGUUUGGCACAGAGGAGAAUGAUGACCAUAACUCACACUCUCCUCCAACUGCCUUAAAUGCUCAGGCUGAUUGGUCAUGUGCUCACCCAACUGCUCCCUAAAUGCUUAACAGAAAAUGAAGACAUCCUCUCCAGAACCCAAGGAAAUACACUUGAAAUGUGAUUUGUACCUCAGAUUGGCAUCCAAGAACUGAAAGAAACACCAGGCAUUCCACACAAUUUCUGGCUCCACAUCCAGUAGAACUAUUGGAAUCCUCCAACAUAACCAUCUUGAGGCAGUAAAUCCUGAAAGAAAGUGAAAGAAGACCUUUCUAAAUAGAGGGAAGUCCCAUCUUACUUGGAUUUAAGUUAUAGUAAAUGAAGAGGAAAAUGCUAACAUGCCAUAUUGGACACCACUUGUCUUUCGAUGCCAGGUCCCUUUUCAGCCGAAUAUGUCAGAAUUUUCUAGGCUCCAUCUUUUCUUUUAUUCCUCUUGCAGCAACCAUAGGCUUUGAUGGCUUCUCACAGGACAGAAAACCUGGAUCAUCCCAAACCUGCUCUGUGAACCCUCUACUUCAUGUAUGGGUUUCCUCCCAUGCUGCACACUGUGAGGGUCAUGCAUCACCACAGCAUGCACAGCUGAGAAAUGUGGAGAGUGAAGGACCCAGGCCACAUUGACUGUGGGGAUGUAAGCCAGUGGAGACACACUUCCUGAAGUAAGAUGCAUUUCACAAAGCUCCCAGUUUCCAGAAGGAUGGAGCACCAGUCACCCUUGGUCAUGGCCAAACCCUCUUUGUCCUUGCCCUUUCCUGCUCUCUGGGAUCACAGAACAUGUGCACUGGACACAGCUUCUGCCUUGGAAACACCCAGACUAAGGUAAUUUCUCACACACCAGUUUAUCUUCCAGCUUCUGUCAGAACUUUAGGUCAGGUAUUAUGAGCCAGAUAGAGUAAAAAAUAUAAACUUUAAAAAUUAUAAUCACCCUCAACAUGGCAAGCUUCUCAUGGUAAGAAAGGAAUGCAAGAAUUCAGAAACUAACCCAGGGAAUAGCAGGCUCAAGAUUUCUUGGCAAAUAAAUUCACUUAAUAGAUCACAGAUAUUUUCUCAUCUCAACACAUGCUGUGCACAGGUAUAUUUCAAACCUAAUCACCGUGGAAUUUCUCAUUUUCAUUAUUACAAACAAAGCUACAAUAAGUUCAUGUGUAUUGAAAUCCUUGCAAACUUGACUAGUAGCUCAAGAUAAAUUUUAGAAUAAAAAAUCAAAUGGUAUUCACAUGUAUAUACUCUGAAGCAUAUAUUUGGUCUUCAACAGGUUUCCAGGCAUACAACUACUAAAAUCCUUGGAUUCCUUAAAGUGGUACUUGUAUGUUAAUGAGUUGACAAAUGGCUAGUAGUCCCUACGUAGCUUCAGGAUGGGAGCUGGGCACCUGAAAGACCAAGGCAGAAUUAGAGAAUUAAGAUAGUCAGACCCAGCCCCCAACCUCCAUGGAGGGAAGAAGGGAUGAAUGUUAAGCAGAACACCAAUGGCCAGUGAUUUAAUCAGUCAUGCCUACAGAAUGAUGCCUCCAUAAAAACCCUCAAGGACUGGGUUCAGAGGGCUUCCAGAUAGCUGAAGACGUGGAGGUUCCUGGAAGGUGGUGAACCUGGAGAGAGCAUGCAAGCUCCACAGCCUUUCCCUAUACCUCACCCUAUGCAUCUCUUCAUCUGCAUCUCUUGCGAUAUCCUUUACAAUAAACUGCUAAAUGUAGAUGCCUCCAUGAGUUCUGUGGGCUGCUCUAGCAAAUUAAUUGAACCCAAGAAGGGGGCUGUGGUAACCCAGACUUACAGCUGAUUGACUGGUCAGACACACAGGUAAAAAGAACUUGAGGCUUAUAAUUGGUAUUGGAAACGGGGAUGUCUUAUGAGACUUAGCCCUCACCCAGCAGACCUGGCGUUAUUUCCAGGUAGAUAGUGUCAAAACUGAAUUGAAGGACACCCAGCUGGUGUCUGCCAUAGGAUUGAUUGUUUGCUUGGUGUAUGGGCUUAACCCCAUCACCUUUAGUCACAGAAGUCUUCUGUGUUGAUUGUUGAGUGAGAGAAUAGAAAAAGCGCUUUAGUUUGUUUUUCCUUAUAGAACAUGUUGACAUUAUGUGGACAUAUUUAAAUUUCCCUUCAGACACCAAAUUCGUACUUUUGCCAAUAAUGUGUACAAAGGCAUAUAUUCUCACAGUUUCACUAACAUUUGAUUUUGUUAGUAACUUUAGUUUUACUUGCAAAUCUUACCUCAGUAUCAUUUUAUUUGGCAUUGAUUUAAUCAUUAGUGAGGUUUAACAUCUUCUGGUAUGUUUUGGGGCUAUUUGUGUUUCUUCAAUAAAUUGUUUUUUUCUUAAAUUUUCAUUGUUUUACCUUUUUGCUUACUGAUUUGUAGCGGUAGUUGACAUGAUUCUACACAUCUUUGUCAUCAUAUAAGUGUUGAAUCGUUUUUCUAGUGGGACGUUUUAUCCUUUUGCUAUGUUUUGUUUGUUUCCUUUGUGGUACAAAAGUUUUAAAUGUUAUAUGUAUUAAAUAAACUAUCAAUCAUGCCUUUAUG